GAUUACAGGCAUGAGCCACCGCACCCAGCCUCUUCCAGACUUUUUUUUGAGCCUGAAUAUGCAUGCAGUACACACAUCACUCUUCAUUAAAUGAUGAAGUUAUAUCAAAUGUUGCCUGUUUUUAAAAACUUAAUGUACUAUGGGACCCCUUCUUCUGUCAGAUAGCCUCAUGAUAUCCCUAGGGUCUCUGUCCGUUGUAGAGAUGCAGCACCAUUUGUUGAAACAAUCUCCCAAGGAUAACUAUUUAAGUUGCUCCCCCAUUUUUAACAUUACAAACAACAUUCUUGUAAAUCCAUCGUUGUUUCUUCCCUGAUUAUUUCCUUAGGCUGAAUUUUUAAAAGAGGAAUUUCUAGGUUAAAGGUCGACUUAAUUCUGGCUAGUUUUGUUUUUAAUGAAAAUAAUUCAAGUAUACGGUAAAAAAAAAAAAAAAAAAAAAAAAAAAUCCCAACAGAACAAAAGUAAGACUUUCUGAAUCCUAUACACUUAACUUUACUUCCUGGUGGAAAUCACCAUAAAAGUUAUAUGCACUCUUGCAGAUAUGUGGAAUUGGUUUUUUAUUGUUGUAAAAUAUAUUUAACAUCAUAAAUUUUACUGCCUUUGCCAUUUUAUGCUUUGCUUUGUUUUUUGAGACAGAGUCUCACUCUGUCACCCAGGCUGGAGUGCAGUGGUGUGAUCACAGCUCACUGCAGUCUUGACCUCCUGGGCUCAAGUGAUCCUCCUGCCUCAGCCUCCCAAGUAGCUGGGAGUGCAGACAUGAGCCACCAUGCCUAGCUGACUUUUUUUAUUCCUUUUGUAGAGACAGGGUCUUACUAUGUUGCCCCCAGACAGGUUUUGAACUCCUAGCCUCAAAGAAUUCUCUCACCUCAGCCUUCCAAAGUGCUGGGAUUACAGGCAUGAGCCACUGUGCCUAGCCACCUUAACCAUUUUUAAGUGUGUAGUUCAGUGAUAUUAAGUACAUUCAUAUAUUUGUGCAACCGUCAUCACUAUCCAUCUCCAGAACUUUUUCAUCUUGCAAAAAUGAAACUCCAUACCCAUUAAACAAUAACCUCCCAUGCCUCCUACCCCUGACCCCGGCAGCUACUGUUCUACUUUCUGUCUCUAUGAAUUUGACUAGGUACUUCACAUAUGUGGAUUCGUGGGGAUAUUUAUUGUCCUCUUAUGACUGACUUAUUUCACUUACCAUGAUGUCUUCAAAGUUCCUUCAUGUUGUGGCACAUAUCAGAAUUUCUUUCGUUUUUAAGGCUGAGUAUUAUUUCAUUCUAUGGAUAUAAUGCAUUUUGUUUAUCUAUUCAUCUGUUGAUGGACAUUUGGGUUUUUUCUAUCUUUUGGCUGUUGUGAAUAAUGCUACAAUGUACAUUGGCAUACCAAUACUUGUUUGAGUCCUUGCUUUCAAUUUUUUAGAUAUAUCUCCAGAAGUAGAAUUGCUGGAUCAUAGGGCAACUCCGAUUUAAAUUUUUGGGGGAACUGCCCUACUGUUUUCUACAGUGGCUGCAUUGUUUCACUCGGUGGAAGUCUCAGCAAUGCAUGAGAGUUCCAAUUUCUCCAUGUCCUCACUUGUUAUUUUCUGUUUGCUUUUUUUUCUUCUUGUAGCCAUCCUAAUGGGUGUGAAGUGGUAUCUCAUUGCAAUUAGAGUUGGUGUUCAUGUUGCCUGUCACUGAGGGGGAAGGAAAUUAUUAUUAUUCUCAUCUUGAAAUGAUGAGUUGGGAAAUAGUCUUAGAAUCACCAUUAACUAGCUGAUCAGUCAUGUAAUCUGAAGAGACUACAAAUCGCUUAAAGGAAGAACACAGCCCCACUGUUCCCAUAGCCCCAAAGAAAAAAAUGAGUGGAGUGCCCAGGUAGUUACUUGGUUUCAGAGGUUUAAUGGUGACCAGGACUGGCUUUUCAUGUUGCCCCAUCCGCUUACCUGAAUCUAUAGUCAAAGGUUUGUUGGAGAGUAGAUUUAAAACAGUUCUCUCGAAAAAAGAUGAAUUUAUCUUUUGUGCAACUGUUAUUAAUAAUUCUAAGCGAUGGUAUCUUAUUCAUCUUACGUAGUGGAUAAAGCUAGUUUUGUGAUUGAUUUUUUUUUUCCUCUUCACCUUCUACUCUGGAAUUCCUUAGGGGUAGAAAAUGAAAGUCCUUUUUUUUUUUUUUACAAAUUAUUUGCUGAAUCGUUUAUUUAAUGAUUCAGUUGGUAGCCUUUAGUGGAGUGUACUAAAGUCUAAGUAUUUAAUUGUGACCCUCUUUUGUUCUUUACUUGUAUUAAUAAUUGUUUUCAUAAUAUUUAUAUCCUGAAGUAUGCAGAUGCAUUUGGUUCCUGAAAUCCAGUUUUAAAAAUUUGGCCAUUAAAACUAUCAUGUCUUUGUACGUAGCUGUCUUUUUCUCUCUGAUAUUCUCACUAGUUGUAAAAUGAUAUUCUAGCCAACUGGCUUUCAGUGGGAUGGAAUGAGUUUAAUGCUAUGUAAAAACUGGCAACUUUAAAAGAAGCUAUCCAGCUUACUUUGACUGCAUGGUGGUGUGUCUUUUCUUACACUUAAAGCAUUUAGAUCACAGAGAUCAGUCAGUCAGCAGCCUGUUUUGUACUUCUCUGUGGCAUUGGAGGCCAUUUAAAAGCUACAGGAUGACAGCCUUAUUCCCAGCUCAGGCUCUUAAUGUUGGAGGCUAGAUCCCAAAUAAAUGUAUAGCCAUAAAUGCUCUAGAAACAAAUGGAAACAUCACAAUAAGCUAUACUUACACCUCUAAUAGAUAUUUUUCUCUCUCUCUAAACCCGGGCUAUAAAAUGAGCAAUUCACAAAAUAAAAGUGUGCUGGAAUUGCCUCUAAAAGACACUUCUUUAUCAAAAGGCCAUCCUCAAGCCAUUUUACGAAUGCCCUGUGACUCAGAAGUGUCACCUCAAUUAAAGUUAUCCUUGAACUCUUAGGAAUCAAAUAGGCAUGGUUUGGCAAAGUGAAGGCAGAAAGUUGAGGUCUGUAUCACUCAGAAGUUGUAUUUCUGUUUUGUCAUUUAAAAUGAGGAAGGUAGAAAUGCUAAAGAUGGAUUUACUGCCUCAUUUUCUUUUUCUUCUUUUACUUGCUAAGAAUUUUCACCCACCAGUGACUUUAAUAUGUUUUGCUCCAUUUGUUUUGGUAACGUCUGCUCAGUCUGUUCUUUUUAUUUUGAAUUCUUAGUUGGGUUCUCAUUGUCUCUCUCUAUUAGAAGCAGCUUUUCUGGAACUUCUUGGGUAACUUUUCUAGAUUAUUCACAAAGUCGAUAACAAGAGGAGUAGUGAUGUAAAAAGUGUCAAUAUUUUUAGAUCCUAGAGUCGUGCAAAACUGUCCUCUUGAUGCAGUGCUUAGCAUUGUCUAGUUACUACAUUGGAAGAACAAGAUGCCUUGUAUAUUUUACGUGUCUAAUCAUAUAUUCAUCUUGCCUCAAACCCCUUUACUCCCUUUACAUUCAGGCAUUGUUAGAAGCUGAGAAAGUAGACAUACAAUACUGUUGUUUUUUCAAUUCAGAAGAGGCUAAAACAUUAUGAAGCUGGUAACUCUAUGCCCACACAUGGAAGUAAUCUGCCUGAGCAAUACCUGUCACAAUAUCAACAUGCAGUAGAGACUAUUGGGAAGAAGUUACCUGCAACUACAGCAACUCCAGACUCAUCAAAAACAGAAAUGGACAGCAGGACAAAGAGCAAGGAUUACUGCAAAGUAAUAUUUCCAUAUGAGGCACAGAAUGAUGAUGAAUUGACAAUCAAAGAAGGAGAUAUAGUCACUCUCAUCAAUAAGGACUGCAUCGACGUAGGCUGGUGGGAAGGAGAGCUGAACGGCAGACGAGGCGUGUUCCCCGAUAACUUCGUGAAGUUACUUCCACCGGACUUUGAAAAGGAAGGGAAUAGACCCAAGAAGCCACCGCCUCCAUCCGCUCCUGUCAUCAAACAAGGGGCAGGCACCACUGAGAGAAAACAUGAAAUUAAAAAGAUACCUCCUGAAAGACCAGAAAUGCUUCCAAACAGAACAGAAGAAAAAGAAAGACCAGAGAGAGAGCCAAAACUGGAUUUACAGAAGCCCUCCGUUCCUGCCAUACCGCCAAAAAAGCCUCGGCCACCUAAGACCAAUUCUCUCAGCAGACCUGGCGCACUGCCCCCGAGAAGGCCGGAGAGACCGGUGGGUCCGCUGACACACACCAGGGGUGACAGUCCAAAGAUUGACUUGGCCGGCAGUUCGCUAUCUGGCAUCCUGGACAAAGAUCUCUCGGACCGCAGCAAUGACAUUGACUUAGAAGGUUUUGACUCCGUGGUAUCAUCUACUGAGAAACUCAGUCAUCCGACCACAAGCAGACCAAAAGCUACAGGGAGGCGGCCUCCGUCCCAGUCCCUCACAUCUUCAUCCCUUUCAAGCCCUGAUAUCUUCGACUCCCCAAGUCCCGAAGAGGAUAAGGAGGAACACAUUUCACUUGCGCACAGAGGAGUGGACGCGUCAAAGAAAACUUCCAAGACUGUUACCAUAUCCCAAGUGUCUGACAACAAAGCAUCCCUGCCGCCCAAGCCGGGGACCAUGGCAGCAGGUGGCGGUGGGCCAGCCCCUCUGUCCUCAGCGGCGCCCUCCCCCCUGUCAUCCUCUUUGGGAACAGCUGGACACAGAGCCAACUCCCCGUCUCUGUUCGGCACGGAAGGAAAACCAAAGAUGGAGCCUGCGGCCAGCAGCCAGGCGGCCGUGGAGGAGCUAAGGACACAGGUCCGCGAGCUGAGGAGCAUCAUCGAGACCAUGAAGGACCAGCAGAAACGAGAGAUUAAACAGUUAUUGUCUGAGUUGGAUGAAGAGAAGAAAAUCCGGCUUCGGUUGCAGAUGGAAGUGAACGACAUAAAGAAAGCUCUACAAUCAAAAUGAAUACUUGAUCAAUGAAAUGUCACAUUAUUCAUCCUGAGUCCGAGACUCAAAUUUUCUGCCCCAGCCAAAAUAAUCUUGUGCCAAAAGAUUAAAGGUUUGCCUCAAAAUGUCCCUGUUUGAAAGAUUAGCACAAAAGUCUUGAUAGCACAACACAAAUUCCAUCCAAGAGGAGAAUCUUCCCCAGGGUUUAGUCCUGGGGCUGGCACUCGUUGUGACUUACACAGAGCAAAAUUGUGCUAAAGGCUUUUCUACUCUGAGAUCUCAAUGCGAAAUGAAAACUCAGGCAGUUUAGUCCAUAGUGGUACUAUUUUGAUGAUAUUUUCCAUUAAUAAAAUGUAAUUUCAGAUUAUUCGUUUACAAGCUUUAUAAUUUUAUGAUUUUUUAAUCGUGUUUUGUCACAGACUUCCCUAGUGUUUGUACUACACGUAGUCAGAAGCGAGUGUCCUUUUCUUUUGCUUCAGGCUAAGAGCUGCCUCGCUCUUUGUCCCCCCAUUAGGAUUCUAUUACAUAUGCAAUUGUAGGUUCAACCUGUCCCUUUCCCUGCCAGCAAACCCCACCACCCUAAGAGAAAUUUUAGCUUAUAUAUGACGGUAUAUUUACAAAAAGAGAAAGAGAAAAUCUGGUAUUUGCAAUGAUCUGUGCCUUCUUUUUACCACCCUCUUGAUUGGAGCUUUUGUGAUGCAGCUACCAUGAUUCAAAAAAAUUAAAAAUUAAAAAAAAAAAAUCUGCCACUUAUCCAAGUCCACUAGAGGCCACUGUCUUCAAAGCUUCUCUCACCCUAGCCAAAGGUCCUAAGAGGAGACAGCUGUGAAGUUGGGCGUGCUCUGUGGUACCAGCUGUGACUUUUCUAUUUCUCCUAGUUUUAGGUUGUUCAUGAAACUAGAAAUGUCAUCCUGCUUGAUUUUUCAUCAGCCAAGUUAAACCCCUGCUUUCUGUCCUUUGCACCUUUUGCGUGAACAGAAUAUGCAUUAUUAAAGCAAAAAUAAAUAAAAGUAAAAUGCAAAUGAAAACAAGGGAGGGAAAGUUGUAUUAUUUCCUGCACUGGGUUACCCGUGUGUGUUAUCGUUUAAACUGUAUUCACAUAAUGUCAUUUGCCUUGCUCACUUGUAACCCCUUCCUCAGGUCCAAGAGAAUGGGAGGAGGGUCAUGUUGAAGUGUAGCCACUGGAACUUUCUUGCAUUUAUGGAGUUGCUUUUUCUUUCCCAAGGAAACUGAUGUUUGCCUGUCCGCUUUAUCUUUGUAGUACAUGAACAGUUCAGCCUUAGACUAUGUAACUGUUUUCUCAUCCUUAGCUGAAAAUGAGGGGCCUACUGUAUUGCGAGACUGUUCAGGGGUAGGGGUGGAGGGGGUGGUCCCUUAAUGGCCCCUGAAGAUGUUGGAUGUGUUUCUCAAAAGCUGCUUUGUCUCUUUCCUGAGUUUAAUAGUGAAACUACUAAACAUUAAUAGAUUUGCACAGCCACAAAGAAUGAGAGUUGAUAAUACCGAAGAAGUGAUGCAAAAACAAAAAAUCACAUUACUGAUCAUUGAUAGUAUUACAAAUAAAUGUCUCUUCCUUUCUCUUCCUCCCUUCCUCCCCCUGCCUUCCUCUUAACCUAUGUGCUCAUCCUUGCUACUUGAGGCUGUUAUUUCCCUCCGAGUAUUUAAGGAGCCCAAACACCUUGGUCUUCCUGGGUGGGGGCAUAAUUAAGGGAAGGGAGUGUAUAAGGAAGGAAACCUCAUACCCUCCAUUCCCAUCCCUGGAUAUAUUGCCUUUUCAGCAGCCUCGGGUUCAGUGUGCUUGGGGUCAGGAGUGCCAGGUUCCCAAGAGCAGCGUAAAACAUCCCUGUACCCCUUGACAGUUAUAAGCAUUUCUGCGUUAAACUUGAAGAUUCCAGAGAUUCCCCACGACCUAAUGAUCUAAGAAUGCAGAUUGGAUUCUUUGAUGUUCAAAUUUCUCAUUUACUUAUGAAAAUCCCUAAUUAUAUAGUUUUAUAUAAUGUGUAUACAGAGUAGGAUUGUUGAUGAAAUUGAGCGGUUGGAACACCCUCAUGGAACACUGGCAACAUGGAAUGUAGAGAGCUGAUGUCUUCCCCCUCAUAGAGGCCAUUGGCUUCCUUUGUAUAAGGAGAGGGAGAAGUGAUUCUGGAAGGAGAAGUUGGUAUGUCUAGCUUCAUUGCGGCCCCUCGGGCUACCCAGCAAGAGGAUUCUGCAUCAAGGAACUGGACGAGCCGCUACCCAAACUGCCACCAUCUUUACUCUUUACAAAAUGGACCCAUCGAGAAUGUUGAAAAGCUUGGAAGUAUCACUUUUGAAAAAAAAAAAAAUUAUUUUGCAUUCAGCAUGGACUCGACCAGGCAUCUAUGGAGAUUAUUUUUUUGCUUCAUUUUAUAAAGUUGUAUUUAGAAAAGUCUUAAGUAUUGUGCUUUGUAAAGAAGAUGAUUAAAAUGAAAUUUUGUGAGAA